CUGGCCGGCCGUCGCGGACUCGGGAGAUGGAGGAAAAGGAGAUAUUACGGCGGCAGAUCCGCCUACUGCAGGGUCUGAUUGAUGACUACAAAACCCUCCACGGCAAUGCCCCGGCCCCUGGUACCCCAGCAGCUUCUGGGUGGCAGCCACCCACUUACCACAGUGGCAGAGCCUUUAGUGCCCGCUACCCUCGUCCAAGCCGGAGGGGCUACUCUUCCCACCAUGGGCCUUCGUGGCGCAAGAAAUACUCCCUCGUGAAUCGGCCCCCGGGACCCUCAGACCCUCCUGCCGACCAUGCUGUGCGGCCGUUGCACGGGGCCCGGGGGGGCCAGCCUCCUGUCCCGCAGCAGCAUGUCCUUGAGAGACAGGUCCAGCUCAGUCAGGGUCAGAACGUGGUCAUCAAAGUUAAACCGCCAUCAAAGUCUGGCUCUGCCAGUGCCUCAGGGGCCCAGCGGGGCUCUUUGGAAGAAUUUGAGGAAACCCCCUGGAGUGACCAAAGGCCCCGGGAAGGUGAAGGUGAGCCCCCUCGGGGACAGCUGCAGCCCUCGAGGCCAACAAGAGCCAGGGGGACCUGCAGUGUGGAAGAUCCUCUUCUGGUCUGCCAGAAGGAGCCUGGUAAGCCCAGGAUGGUGAAGUCAGUGGGCAGUGUGGGCGACAGCCCCCGGGAGCCCCGCCGGACAGUCAGUGAGAGUGUGAUUGCCGUCAAGGCGAGCUUCCCAUCCUCCGCUCUGCCCCCACGCACUGGCGUGGCCCUGGGCCGGAAGCUGGGUUCUCAUUCCGUGGCCAGCUGUGCUCCACAGCUCCUUGGGGACAGGAGAGUAGAUGCUGGCCACACAGAUCAGCCAGUUCCGUCUGGCUCAGUGGGGGGCCCCGCCAGACCGGCCUCAGGACCCAGGCAGGCCCGGGAGGCCUCGCUGGUUGUGACCUGUCGAACUAACAAGUUCCGGAAAAACAACUACAAAUGGGUGGCUGCCUCCUCGAAGAGUCCCCGGGUUGCUCGGAGGGCCCUCAGUCCCAGAGUGGCUGCAGAGAAUGUGUGCAAGGCCUCUGCUGGCAUGGCAAACAAGGUGGAGAAGCCGCAGCUCAUAGCUGACCCAGAGCCCAAGCCCAGGAAGCCAGCCACGUCCUCCAAGCCAGGGUCUGCCCCCAGCAAGUACAAGUGGAAGGCCUCCAGCCCCUCUGCCUCCUCCUCUUCCUCCUUCCGUUGGCAGUCGGAGGCCAGCAGCAAGGACCAUGCCUCCCAGCUCUCCCCAGUCCUGUCUAGGUCCCCGUCGGGGGACAGACCAGCAGUAGGACACAGUGGCUUGAAGCCCCUCUCUGGGGAGACCCCGCUCUCGGCUUACAAAGUGAAGAGCCGCACCAAGAUCAUCCGGAGACGCAGCAGCACAAGCCUUCCUGGAGACAAGAAAAGCGGCACCUCACCUGCCGCCACCGCCAAGAGCCACCUCAGCCUCCGGCGGAGACAGGCCCUCAGGGGGAAGAGCAGCCCUGUCCUGAAGAAGACCCCCAACAAGGGCCUGGUACAGGUCACCACGCACCGACUAUGUCGCCUGCCACCGAGCCGGGCCCACCUCCCCACCAAGGAAGCGUCCAGCCUGCAUGCCGUGCGGACUGCACCCACCAGCAAGGUGAUCAAGACCCGCUACCGCAUUGUCAAGAAGACGCCGGCCUCGCCUCUCAGCGCCCCGCCCUUCCCCCUGUCUCUGCCCUCCUGGCGGGCCCGGCGGCUCUCACUAUCCAGAUACCACUGUCCUUGCAAGGGCCGCAUGAAGUUUGCUGAGGUCACCACGCCUUUCCAGGGAGCUGAGCCGGAUUUGCUGUGUGGUCUUCGGAGGGGCUGUCCCAGGGCCUGGGAGUGGGGGGAUGUCUGCUGUGAGUCUCUUUAGACAGCAGUGACCUGAGGGGUCCUUGAGGGCCUAGGCAGGAUUCCUGGCCAGCCUGCCCCUCAGUAGCUGGCACAGACAGAGUGGGUCCUGGGCCGAUGACCCAGCCCAAAGGGUGGCACAGGUGCAGAGGGUCGCGGGCCCGCCAAGGACAGCUGCACCUGGCCGCCUGGCACCUCUGCCGGACGAGCUGAACUCGGCACUCCGGGGCCAUGAAGUCCCACUAAUACUUGUUUUUUUGCAGCUGACAUACAAAACACCAAUAGCUUCAGCUGAAAUGGAUUUUUAAAAGUGUCAUUUUAUGGAGAAUUUUACUUUCCAUCUUGUUGUUUAUUAGGCUCUUAAAGGGAAAGCUUGUAAUGCAUCCAUUGAUCGAAAUACCAAUUGAAUAGAUGUGAGCACAUAAAAUACAUAAAAUAGUCCCAGCCCCUCAUAAUGGAGCACGACGUUUGUAACGGAGGCAGUGUCAUUAGUAUUGCCCCCUGCCACCCAGCCAGGCUGCAGAGGCGCCUCCGAAUCCUUCUUAUUCAUUACUGGGGUGAGACGGGGCAGGGAUGGCCCUCGGAAGGACCAGUGCCCAGUGAGGAAGUCCUCAGAUGUCACAACAGAGCCUCCACCCCACGAGUCAGCCCAGGGGCCGGGGGAGCCAGCCGUGCUCAGCCUCAGCUGGACCAGUCGCACUCAAGGCUGUCCCUGUCCUCAGGGGCCCCCAAACAAGGCUGCUGUCCCUAAGGCUGCAUGGCUCUUUCCCCUCAUGGCGCCCCUGGCCGCUGGUGCAGGGCUCUCAGCUCCCACCCAGGCCUGUAACCCUGCCUGCCUGCUGAAGGUGUAUCCUGGAAAGCCAAGCGGCUGGACGGUCUCUGCAGGCCCCCAUACUGGGAGGUAGAUGCUGUGGGGGUGACAGCGGGACUAGAGAGCCCAUCUGGCCAUGGUGCCGGAGCCCCUGCUGAACAGCAGCUACUGCCCCAGGUACCUGGAGGCCCCUUGGAGCUGGUGAGGGCCCCACGGUCUGGGUAUAGGGGUUUGGAGGAUAGGGGGCCAGACUUGUGAGGAGUAAGUUAGAAGAGGGUUCUUUCUGUGAGAUGAGGUGGCCAUAGCCAUCGUGAGGCCUGCGUGGCCACCACGUAGUCAGAUUUCAGCCCUGGCAGCCACAGGCCCUUGAGCAUUUAGCCCUGCCCCUGAGAUCGUGGGGGCAGGGUCCAGGAGCCGGGAGCCCGCCUAGCACCCCCACUGCACGCCUCUGCUCUGUCUGGCCUGAGCGCCCCUCCCUGCCGGCCCAGCUUGGGCCCCUCCCAUGAGGGACUCUGUCUUCCUCCUCCGGAACUCAGGACAUUCUGUGAGUGUCUGUCCAGUAGAACCACCUCCCCUGCAUUGCCCCAGCCUCACGGGCUGGGCCUCUCCAGCCAAGGGCCCCAUGUAGCCUGGCCAACCCAUUCGGGGGCCGCAGUGGCUCAGCACCAGGAGAAACCGGGAGGGAGGCUUCCAGCCAGCCCCACACGCGCACACGCAUGGACACACAUGCAUGCUCGCCCUCCCGAGCCAGCACGGUGAUGGGGGUGUCAGCGUUUCCAGUGGAAAGCCCCACUUAAGCAGUUUAGUGCCUGUCAUGGCGCAGCUCUGCCUGACCUACUUGGGGAUUCGCUGCGGCGCCGCCUCCCCCCGGCCGCUCCUCUUCUGCUGACUUCGCACUCCCCGCUCGGGCUCCAAGCUUCGAAAAAUUGUGCUCCAUUUCCUGAAAAUGCUUCUCCGGUUGUUUUCUCUGUGUCUCAGCUGGACUGCCUGUUUACUGCACGUUGCCACUGGCCUGGGCGGCCUGGCCAGGGGCUGCUGGGUCCCCGGCCCACACACAGACACAACCCCGGCCUAGAAGGCCCUGAGGUCGUGUCCCCGUGGCCCGGUACCUGCUCCUGUGGUCCUGCCUCUUCUGGCUGCUAGGGCCGGGCCAAGACCUCGCUCAGCCCUUGGCCUCUCCUGCUGUCACCAUACUUAUGCCCCCGAGGGUCUUUCCACGUCUGCAUAUUGCACGUCCCUGUGUCACGUCCGUAGCAGCCUUGCCAUCGUCCUGGGGAGACAGGGACAGGCUCGCCCUUCUCGGAGCUCUCAGGGCAUGUGUUCUGACCAUGCCUCCCUCCUUGAGCCCCGCUGCUCCCUUUGUUCUCAGAGAGCCCAUCUUGCCCCAGCCCGCAUUCCCAGCGCCUGGCCCUUGCUGCCUGAGCCCACUCCUUGUAUCUGCUGACCAAGCCCUGGCAGCCACCUCUCUGCCACAGGUCUCCUUCCUGAGUGUCUGUAACUGACCAGGGCCUCCUGACCCUUCCCCACCCCACACUCCUCCCUUAGGACCUCUUAAGGUCCUGGGAGCCCCAGGGUGGCACACACUUGGGUGUGUUCUCGCAACACACAUUUACAGAGCCCCCUGCGUGCCCGGCACAUCCGCAGGGCCAGGGGUGCAGCAGUGGUCUUUGCAGAUACGGCCCCUGUGCUCAUUUUCCCCAGUGGUAAGUAGGGCCGGCCUCCCCAGUGCUGUGACAUCUGCACUUGGCCUCAGGCCUGCCCUGGGAUCUGGACAGAGGGACAGCACGUGCAAAGACCUGGCGCCAGGAGGGAGCACAGUGCUUUCCAGAAACCAGAACUUCCCAGGAGAACUGGAGUUCUAGGCUGGAGAGAGGCUGCAUGGGGGCUGUGGCCAGCAGGACCUGAGUGCCUGGCCCUGCAGGGCUUUCUAACCUGGUCAUCUUGAGAACGAGGGGACCCACUGCAGGGUCUUGGCAGGGACUUGAUCAAAUGUGCAGCUUUCAAACCAACUGGCAGGGUGGGGUGGGUGCAGCCCCCUUUCAGCUGUGAACCAGGGCGGAGACCCAGCUGGCUCAGUGCCGGCCUGGGGCUCUGCGUGGCAUGUUCAGGGCCUGGGCAUUGCCUCGGGGCAGGGCUUCUGCCAGUGGUGAGGCUGAGGGCCCUGGGCAGGGGGUCCGAGUGGAGGCUGAUGAGGCCCCUCAUGGGGAGAACUGCUGACCGACACUGGCUGCGGGGCCUGGCUGUGGGAGCAGGAGGGCCAGCUAGUGCUGGAGUGUGUUUAAAAGACAAGACUGGAGCUGGAUUGGCAGCAGCCGGAGGUGCAGAGCGACAACACGAGGGUCCUGGAAGGUCCCCAUCGUCCCUGUCUGCCUUCAGUUUCCCUCCCAGGGUCUGAUGUCCCCUCGCCGGCUCCACCGUGUGGCGGCGCUUGGCAGGAAGAAAUCUUCAAAUCCCAGCCCUCCCUGCUGUGGAGCCCCUGGCGGGUCUGGAGGGUCUGGGAGCAGCUCUCCCCUCUGCUGGCCUCGCCUCUCCCGCCCCUGGUCACACAGCGACCUCUCUGUUCCCAGGUGUUCUCCUCAAGCACAGACACAACCUCACGGAGUUCUCAGGGGCUCACGUGGGGUGGGAUGUCACCGAGGCUGGCAUGGGAACUUCGGUGGCGGGGAGGGAAGGAUGCUGAGGGGCUGCUAUGGGGAAGGAGCCCCUGGUUCCCAUCAGCAGCUCUCCUCCAGAUGAGGGUCUCUGGCCCCACUGUGGUCUGUGUUGGCCUUUGUGUAGCCGCUGGUCGCACCACUGGGCCUGGGAGCUGGGUUGGGAGGUGCUCCGGAGAGGCCCAGCCUUCCCAGGGCUGCCUGCAAUCUGGCCUAGGCCUCGAACCCCUGGCCACAUGACCCAAGGCCUUGGAAGACCCUGUUGAACAAGCCACAGAGCCUCAGGGAGGGUGUCCUGGGCAGCAUGUGUCUGAAGGUGCUGUGGGACUGGGCAAUCGGAAGAUACAGCUUUUGGGCUUAAAAGCUGCCUGUCUGUGGCCUGGACCCUCGGGUCCCACCAGUGUGUGUCCCGCCGGGGCAUCCUGGGUGCUGGGCUGCUUCCCGGGUCUCUAGGGUGGAGGAGGCCUCCCCCAGUCCCCUUACCACCUCUGCCUGAGUCAAGAGACCGGGCCCCUUCCCCAGCCUUCCUGCCAUGCCAGUGUGCCAGUCACGCUGACUACCAGGCCCAGCAUUCUCUGAUUGGUCUCAGAGCUGGGUCGCAUGGCACGGAGACACCGCAGGCAGUGCCCAUGGCAGGGAGCAGGACCUGAAAGGGCCCGGGUGCUCAGAGGGCUGGACUCACCCGAGGAGCCGCAUUGGUUUGUCAGAUGUGUUUCUGCUGAGCUGGGGCUUCUGCUGCUGGGAGCGCAAGUGCUGAGGCUGUCACCCUGGGGGCAGGCAGUGCACUGGGCCUGCUUGCUGUGCAUGCACUGCCCUGACUGCGAGGCCACUGAUCUGGGCCACGUGUAUGUGUGCAUCUGUGCCCAGGAUCAAUGACGUGGCCUGGGGUGAGGCCCCUCUCAGCCUGCACGGCCCACAUGACAUGGCGCGGGGGCUGCUCUGACCUGCCACGGGCAGUGCCCUCGGAGUGGGUAGAGUGUGGGUGUCCAGGGUUGGUCCUCAGAGUCCUUGCAUGGGCCACUUGGCAGCAGUGGCCCAGGCCAGGGCUUGCAGGCCCGGGAGCCUGGCAGCUGGCAGGCUGUGCGUGGGCAUGCCUUGUGGAUGCCGGCAGGGGAUGCACCAGGUUUGCCCCUGGGCUUUCAGGAAAACCAAGACCUCAGAGUGAGCCUCUCUCCCAUCUUGCCCAGGCCCCCAGCACCACUGAAGUCCUGGGGACAGGUGACAGGAGUCCCUGAGGGUCGAGAGCCAGAGGUCCGCCCGGCCCCCACUGUUGCUACCUGUGCCUAGCGAGGCUGGCAGCACUCAGCAGGUCCGAGGGGCCCAGGCUGAGGCAGGACAGGGGCUUUCAGAGACAGGAGGGCCUGGGCUCAGCCCUCUGGGCACCUGUGGUGCCCCUCGCCAGCCCGGGCAGCCUCUGGCCUGCAAGUUUCCAGCUACUCCUAAGGCAGUACUGCACAGACAGCUUCUUCAUACACCUGCUUUUGUAGUGUGUGUGUCUUUCUCCCCAUUACUGCUGCUUUUCAUUUAAAAUGUUAUCUCCCCCUCCUGGCCUUUGUCCCCCCCCAGGGAGGAGAGGGGAGGCCCAGCCUCGCCCUGGUGUAGUCAAGGUUAUGGUGAUAAAUCCUGGGGCAUUGUCACUUCUGUUCGGAGUAAAUUGGCUGGCUGCUUUUGGGCUGAAGGAAAGAUAAUUUGCUGUAGUAUUUCAAAUGGAUUAGAAAUGGAUUUGAAGGGAAAGUUCAUGCCUCCCAUUACAAAGGCGAGAAAGAAGACUAUCUUAAGGCACUGUUCCCUCCCUGGCCUUCAUUAUCCACGCUUAAUACCUUUCCUAUUUUCCAGCGUUAAUGAAAUUUCCUGGCAGCGUGGGCCUGCCGGACGGAUGGGAGAGGCCUUUAGAUCUGCAGCUCCCGUUGCGGAAAAGGAAUUACAGAGCCUUCCGUGAGGGCAGACGCGCGCUCCGGGUCCUUGGCCCUGCUAUUAUCUCAUUAAUUUCAUCCCCCUUCUCAAUGCAGUUCGUUUCCAAAGGCCAUCCUCUCCAUUAGGGUCACAAUUUACUGGAGUGCUGUGACACCCACGGCCGUGAAAAGCUACAAGGCCCUCGCCCCAUGCCCUCCCAGCACCCUCCUGCUGUAGGUUCCAAAGCCAGCCAGGCAGCCAGGGCGAGGGCAGGGGUGAGGGCAACCCUAGACAGCUCUCCGUCACCCCCGCCAACCUGCACAGGCCCGACGUUCUGCCACAGCAUCUUCCCAGGAUGCAGCUUCUCGGAAUGAGGCUCUUGGGCUAGGUGUGCUGAGCACCAGGAAGCGCCCUGCCCCAUUCCCGGGAGGCCCUGGGCUCCCAGGCUAUGGUGGGCAGUGGGGGGCUGGGAACAUUCCCAAGCAUGAAGAGCGGGCGCAGAUCCCGGGACGGCUCAGCAGGGGCUGCCACAUCUCCAUUCCGCCCAGAUCCUCUAAUGUCCUCUGGGUGUUCUCACACUCCAGUAAGGUGUUUUUUUUAGGAGGGAAGAGAAGGGGACAAGCUAAUUGUUCAUGUUCAUCCAUGAGAAUGAGCAGGGGCGGCUGGGCGCAGUGGCUCAUGCCUGUAAUCCCGGCACUUUGGGAGGCCAAGGCCGUCAGAUCACCUGAGGUCAGGAGUUCGAGACCAGCUUGGCCAAUGGGGUGAAACACCAUCUCUACCAAAAAUACAAAAAUUAGCCGGGCGUGUUGGCACAUGCCUGUAAUCCCAGCUACUCUGGAGGCUGAGGCAGGAGAACCUCUUGAACCCGGGAGGCGGAGGUUGCAGUGAGCCGAGAUCGCACCAUUGCACUCUAGCCUGGGUCACAAGAGCAAAACUCCAUCUCAAAAAAACAAAAAAAUAAGAAGGAGCGGGGGCAUGGCUGCUGUAGUGCCCAGCCAGGCCGAGGUCCUGAAACAGAGCUGAGGGGCGGCCCUGGUGGGUGGGGCGGUCCUGGAAGCUUCCAGUGCCUGCUGACCCCCAGAGGCCCUGAUGCCUCUGCCCCACGGGCCCUUCCCUGGGCCUGGCCAGCUGUGGCUGCCCCUGGGGGAGGGGAGCAAGUGCUGCAGCCCGGGCCUCGCCCUCCAUCCGGGUGCCUUUGGAGAGCCACACAGUGAGUGGGUGGUGGCCUGUCCCCAUGUGAGCCUCAGUCAGGGGGACACUCCUGCAGGUGAGUCCUUGCACACCUGGGUUCUGGGCCUCCCUCCCAACCAUCUCCUCAGGGAGUCCUGGCUGGACCCAGGUGGAGAGCUGGGUUGGCUCUGUUGCCUGCUCGUCCUUCCUGCUUUGUGGCGGCCAGGGUUGAACCCAGCCUGUGCCGUGGGCGGGGUCAGGCAUGCAGGAUUGGGUGCUUCCCCCGAGAGUGCAGACUUACCAUCUACUCACUGGAGCCUGUGGGGAGGCAGGGAGCUGGGGGCUCCCGGGAGCAAGUCCAGGCUGGCCCUGAGCAGCCUUUCCGGGGCGAGGACCACAGUUAGCUUUGGCCCCAGUUGUAUGAUGGCCAGAGGCUCUGUGAGUGGCUGGUGCUGCGGUGGGGGGGUGCACCCUGGCCACCAGCCCCCUCACCCUCCCAAUGGUGAGACCCCUGAGGCCUGUGAGUACUGUGGGGCUGGUGCAGGGCCCUGGGCUCAGCCUGACUGGGAUUUGGGGUCAAGCUGAGUGUCCCCCAGGUAGUGGCCGUAGCUCCUGUGGAAGGUCAGAACCUGCCUCUGAGCCCCCCAGGCUGAUGGGGUUCUCCAACUGAGAGGCUGGUGCAGGAGGUCCUGCCUGGCCUGCCUCCCUCCAGGCCUGGUGCCAGGAUAAGCUGAAGGUACAGGCCAUGCACCUGCUGGGCCUGCAGGCACCUGGAGGCCGGGGCUGCACUGGGACCCCAGGGUCUGAUGAGAGCCUGGAGGUCUGAGUCUGGCUGGCAGGAUGCCUACCCUCCACCCCUCUGGCCCAGACAGUGCCCGGCUGGGGGUUGGGGAGCAGCUGGAGUGUGCAGGGCGCAGACAGGAUAGGUGGGAGGUGGGGGCCAGCAGACCACUCAGCACUGCCAGGCCCCUUGGUGGGCUCUUUCCCGCCAAGAUUGGUGUUUGUGAACUUGAAUUUUAAUUAAAGGAAACUGGGUUAAGUGCUCCAGCCGCCGUGCUUGUACUUACACUGCAGCUCCCAUCCCCGGCACCGGGCUCUCUCUGCUCCCAUUCUCUCUCUAAUGGGCCCUUGGAGGCCCCCGGCUGCUGAGAAUUACCCCAGCUUGCAGGCAGAGGGACCAAGGCCCGGAGGGGUUGCAGGGCUGAGUGGUGGGGAUGGCGGUGGAACCCGACAGAAGGGCUGCUCCAUCCCCAGUACCACCAGGUCUGUUGGCUCCUCGUGGGUGGCUUUGAUGGAUAUGCUGCUGUCCCCCUGUACCUGCCCCAUCCAGCCAGACAAGCGAGCCCCACCUUCAUGCAUGCUGCGGGCCUGGGUCUAGGGGGCACCCCACCCUGGCCCAGACCAGCUGGAAAAGGGUCUCCUGCGGCUGUGGAUGGGUUGGGGGGCUCAGGUACUCCACAGCAGAGAGGGCUGUGUAGCUGCAGGGCCAUGGGGACCAGUGUGGGAUGGGGAGCGUAGAGCAGGGGCACAGCCCUGUGCCAGGCCUGAGCUGCCCGUCCUCGCCUCCCACUUGACUGGUCCCUUUGCUGCCUGCGCACCCAUGGCUGCCCAAAAAUGUCUUGCCCAGAUUUGCUGGGGGUGUGGUAUCCACCUCAGGGGUCAUGGCAGCUUGAGCAGAGCGUGAGCUCAUGUGGAAUCAAGCUCAAUUUGCCAGGCCCUGAGCCCCCCACCUUGGGGGCUGCUUGCCCGAGGGUCCGCAGGGCUGUGGGUGUGGCUGGCAGCUGCAGGGAGGUGCCUCUGGAGUGCAGCUCAGGCCCCUCUUGUCUUACUCUGCCCCUUGGCUUCCUGGAGGCUGUGGAGUAUUUGGCAGGAGUGGGGGCUGCCAGGGCUCAGGGUCUGUCGGCCUAGGUCUCUUCCUCUAGCCAGGGUCAUCAGCUCAGCUAACUCCAGGGGCUGUCGCGGCCUCUUCAGCCCUUGGACUUGAGGCAACAUCAGCAUUUCCCUCAAACAGCCUGGCCCGGGGUCUGUGAGGCUGUCCCCAUGCCCUCUCAGUGCAGGGCUCUCUGAGCUGUGGAUGAAGGGGAGGCAGGACAGGGUGGAGGAGGAGAAGAGGCAGGGUAGCCUGCUGACCCUAUGGUGUCUGUGGUCCUGACGGCCAGGGUGGUAUGUGCUGGGGCCGGUUGGUAGAAAUAGCCCCAGCCUUGAAGCCGACUCAAGGGAGCCUCAGCCCAGGUGCCAAGGGCCAGGUGUGCUUCUCACCAACACGCAGACACCUUGCAGCCCCUCUGCCCUGCAGCCCCAGGGACCCUUACCCUGCAGCACACAGCCAGGUGGUCAGGGCCCAGGGGUGGUUAUAUCCACGGGGAGGUGUGCACUGGAGGACGACGCUGCCCUCUCACCGUGGCUUCUAGGGGCGCAUGAGUUCCCAGCCUCGUGGGUGGGGUCGGGGGCGCCACCUCCUGGGACUCCUUGUCAGUGUUCCCUGAUGACGGCCAAAAUGUCCCUGAGGUGGGGGUUGGGGGCCAGAGGGGGACAGAGGUCUCUUGGCAGCUGGGCCAAUGGCCCGUGGUCACCCAGCUGGAGUGUGUACCCACCGCAAGUGCUGCUCCCUGUCCCCCUUGGGAGGCCAGGCCUGGGCUCGGCCCCUGGCACUGACCAUCAGAGCUGUAGUCUGUCCUGGGGCCAGGUUUG